GCCGCGGCUCCCGCUCGCGCCGGCGCUGCACGGUAGUCAGCCCGCCGCCGCCGCCUGCUUUGUGCUUCCCACAGAAGAUGGGAGCGACCUCUUCCUGAUCGGGAGCUGUUUAAAAGGAGGGAGUGCGCCGUAUUUUCUACUAGCGUGGAGGAACGGAGGAAGAAUCCAUUCACACUCCCCAAACCAGGGAUGUCAUGGUCUAGAACACCUAUGCUGAAGUACAAGGCUGAGCAAGAAAGAUCACUCCACUGCAACUGAGCAAAGUGCUGAAGGAGUUGAAAGGAAGAAGAGAACAUUGGACGUGGUUUCACGGAGGAGGAAGCAUUUUAAUUUAUUCAGAAAGAGUGAAAAGGAUUUUGAAAGCAAAUAAGGCUAGCCACUUUUGAAACAUGUCAAAGAGCCCCAGCUUAUUUACGACAAGGUAACCGUGGAGAAAUGUUAGGGCAGUUUCUAGACCCUUUCAUUCCGUUCUGUGUCCCAGUCAGGACCAUGCCACAGAAACAGGAUCUGAAACAAAUAACAACAUAAGCCAUUGUACAAAUGCAUUUUAUACUUGAAACCAAAAUGUAGGAUGAACUUCCAGCAUGGCCUUGGAGGAGAGAGGCUAUACCAGUCAGAGGUUGUGACAGUUGGAAGUGUCAUGUACAACAUGCGGCGAUUAAGUCUUUCACCCACCUUUUCAAUGGGAUUUCAUCUGUUAGUUACUGUGAGUCUCUUAUUUUCCCAUGUGGACCAUGUAAUUGCUGAGACAGAAAUGGAAGGAGAAGGAAAUGAAACUGGUGAAUGUACUGGAUCAUAUUACUGUAAGAAAGGGGUGAUUUUGCCCAUUUGGGAACCCCAAGACCCUUCUUUUGGGGACAAAAUUGCUAGAGCUACUGUGUAUUUUGUGGCCAUGGUCUACAUGUUUCUUGGAGUCUCUAUCAUAGCUGAUCGGUUCAUGUCCUCUAUAGAAGUCAUCACAUCUCAAGAAAAAGAAAUAACCAUAAAGAAACCCAAUGGAGAGACCACCAAGACAACUGUGAGGAUCUGGAAUGAAACAGUUUCUAACCUGACCUUGAUGGCCCUGGGAUCUUCUGCUCCUGAGAUUCUCCUUUCAGUAAUUGAAGUGUGUGGCCAUAACUUCACUGCAGGAGACCUCGGUCCUAGCACCAUCGUGGGAAGUGCUGCAUUCAAUAUGUUCAUCAUUAUUGCACUCUGUGUUUAUGUGGUGCCUGACGGAGAGACAAGGAAGAUUAAGCAUUUGCGUGUCUUCUUUGUGACAGCAGCCUGGAGCAUCUUUGCCUACACCUGGCUUUACAUUAUUUUGUCUGUCAUAUCUCCUGGUGUUGUGGAGGUCUGGGAAGGUUUGCUUACUUUCUUCUUCUUUCCCAUCUGUGUUGUGUUCGCUUGGGUAGCGGAUAGGAGACUUCUGUUUUACAAGUAUGUCUACAAGAGGUAUCGAGCUGGCAAGCAGAGGGGGAUGAUUAUUGAACAUGAAGGAGACAGGCCAUCUUCUAAGACUGAAAUUGAAAUGGACGGGAAAGUGGUCAAUUCUCAUGUUGAAAAUUUCUUAGAUGGUGCUCUGGUUCUGGAGGUGGAUGAGAGGGACCAAGAUGAUGAAGAAGCUAGGCGAGAAAUGGCUAGGAUUCUGAAGGAACUUAAGCAGAAGCAUCCAGAUAAAGAAAUAGAGCAAUUAAUAGAAUUAGCUAACUACCAAGUCCUAAGUCAGCAGCAAAAAAGUAGAGCAUUUUAUCGCAUUCAAGCUACUCGCCUCAUGACUGGAGCUGGCAACAUUUUAAAGAGGCAUGCAGCUGACCAAGCAAGGAAGGCUGUCAGCAUGCACGAGGUCAACACUGAAGUGACUGAAAAUGACCCUGUUAGUAAGAUCUUCUUUGAACAAGGGACAUAUCAGUGUCUGGAGAACUGUGGUACUGUGGCCCUUACCAUUAUCCGCAGAGGUGGUGAUUUGACUAACACUGUGUUUGUUGACUUCAGAACAGAGGAUGGCACAGCAAAUGCUGGGUCUGAUUAUGAAUUUACUGAAGGAACUGUGGUGUUUAAGCCUGGUGAUACCCAGAAGGAAAUCAGAGUGGGUAUCAUAGAUGAUGAUAUCUUUGAGGAGGAUGAAAAUUUCCUUGUGCAUCUCAGCAAUGUCAAAGUAUCUUCUGAAGCUUCAGAAGAUGGCAUACUGGAAGCCAAUCAUGUUUCUACACUUGCUUGCCUCGGAUCUCCCUCCACUGCCACUGUAACUAUUUUUGAUGAUGACCACGCAGGCAUUUUUACUUUUGAGGAACCUGUGACUCAUGUGAGUGAGAGCAUUGGCAUCAUGGAGGUGAAAGUAUUGAGAACAUCUGGAGCUCGAGGAAAUGUUAUCGUUCCAUAUAAAACCAUCGAAGGGACUGCCAGAGGUGGAGGGGAGGAUUUUGAGGACACUUGUGGAGAGCUCGAAUUCCAGAAUGAUGAAAUUGUCAAAACAAUAUCAGUCAAGGUAAUUGAUGAUGAGGAGUAUGAGAAAAACAAGACCUUCUUCCUUGAGAUUGGAGAGCCCCGCCUGGUGGAGAUGAGUGAGAAGAAAGGUGGCUUCACAAUAACAGGCCAACCUGUCUUCAGGAAGGUUCAUGCUAGAGAACAUCCGAUUCUCUCUACUGUAAUCACCAUUGCAGACGAAUAUGAUGACAAGCAGCCACUGACCAGCAAAGAGGAAGAGGAGAGGCGCAUUGCAGAAAUGGGGCGCCCCAUCCUGGGAGAGCACACCAAGUUGGAAGUGAUCAUUGAAGAAUCCUAUGAAUUCAAGAGUACUGUGGACAAACUCAUUAAGAAGACAAACCUGGCCCUUGUGGUUGGGACUAACAGCUGGAGAGAACAGUUCAUUGAAGCUAUCACUGUCAGUGCUGGGGAAGAUGAUGACGACGAUGAAUGUGGGGAAGAGAAGCUGCCCUCCUGUUUCGAUUACGUGAUGCACUUUCUGACUGUGUUCUGGAAGGUCCUGUUUGCCUUCGUCCCCCCUACUGAAUACUGGAAUGGCUGGGCGUGUUUCAUUGUCUCCAUCCUCAUGAUUGGCCUACUGACAGCUUUCAUUGGAGACCUGGCUUCCCACUUUGGCUGCACCAUUGGCCUGAAAGAUUCUGUGACUGCAGUCGUGUUCGUCGCACUUGGAACAUCAGUGCCAGACACAUUUGCCAGCAAAGUGGCAGCCACCCAGGACCAGUAUGCAGACGCCUCCAUAGGUAACGUCACGGGCAGCAACGCGGUGAAUGUCUUCCUGGGAAUCGGUGUGGCCUGGUCCAUCGCUGCCAUCUACCACGCAGCCAAUGGGGAACAGUUCAAAGUGUCCCCUGGCACACUAGCUUUCUCUGUCACUCUCUUCACCAUUUUUGCUUUCAUCAAUGUGGGGGUGCUGCUGUAUCGGCGGAGGCCAGAAAUCGGAGGUGAGCUGGGUGGGCCCCGGACUGCCAAGCUCCUCACAUCCUGCCUCUUUGUGCUCCUAUGGCUCUUGUACAUUUUCUUCUCCUCCCUGGAGGCCUACUGCCACAUAAAAGGCUUCUAAAGGAACUAUCAGAUAUAGUAAAUUUAUAUAUAUACAUAUAUAUACAUAAAAAUUAUGUAUAAUGGACAGAGGAAACUGACAUUUGUCAUGUUCACUUACCUGCUGAUGGAAUCCAGCUUCAAGAGCAUACUCUGUACUAGGGCCGAAGUAAAAAACCAUCACCUCCCAUUCCCAGGGGCAUCAUCAUGUUCAACAAGGCAUGGAGGCAGGGCCAUCUUUGCAGCUCAGUCUAGAAGGGCUGCACUCUCUCCAGGUUGAUAAAUCCUUAAGGCUUUGAUUUGUUUUGUUUUUGGUUUUGUUUUCAGUGGAGCUGGGGAGGUAGUUAAUGUUUGGCUUUAUUUUUGUUAUUUUGUUUUGUUUUGUUUUUUUGGGAGAGUCAGGGUUGUUGCUUUUCUUUGUGGAAAGUGAAACCAUCCAAAUGUAAAUGGGUUUUGGUAAAAAUUUAAAUCAUUAGUAUUCCCCCUCACCUCCCCCAAUCACUUUAAAACUUAUUUUGGAUUAAGAAAAAAUCUGGGCAUGGAAGAAGAAAGAAGCAUGUCUUCAUCGUAUUACCAAAGUUCAUGCUUAUCUCCGGAAUGUGAGUGGAGGUGAAGCUGCCUCCAAGAAGAAGCAUAAAAGUGGAAUGGAGCCAGGAAAUCCGAUGGUUCUAGAAAUAGUCUGAUAUUUAAACAUGUGAUACCUGGCAGUCUCGUUUAACAGGUACAAGGAAAACGUGCCUAGAUUCCCAGGAACGUGCAAAAUCCUUUCUUUCUUAUCUCUUUAGCUCUGGACUGUGAUUGGCAAGGUCCUUCUUCCAGCAUUCAGCCCAGCUAAGCCCCCAGGUGCCCCAUCCCAACCCUGUUCCUCCUGUCCACCUGCCAUCCCCUAUGCAAACAGUAAGAAUAACCCCAUUCAAAAAGCACAUCAUCGUUUUCCAUUUGCAUUAACAUGUGUCUCAGUCCCAUGUUGCCGUUGCUUGGGAUUGUCUGUCAGUUUUAUUUUCAAAGGCAUCCAUGGCUUGCACAAUCCUGUUCCAGUCAUGACUGAACAUUUGCUCCUUCUUCAUGUGCCGUUCGGAAAUGUUGUUGUGAUACCUGUUACACAGUGCAUGGUGAAAAACAAAUAAAACAAAACAAAGAGUAUCUGUAUAUAGUAGAGUAUAGUACAUACUGUUCUCCCAUUUGGCAAUGUUGAUUGGACAUUGAAGACAUAAGUGAGUUUUCUUUUCACCUGAGUUGUUACUUUUGUGCUGUUAUUGAGUUUGAUUAAUUACUAGGGAUAAAAGGAGAAAAUGGAUUAUUGUUCACGGUUCUGCACAUUCAUUUCUAAGAAGCAAUAACUGUCAUGUGGGGAGAAGUUAAAGCUAUUGAGAGGAUAGCAGGCAAACUACAAAGAUCUUCAUGGAAAAUUAGCCAUGUGGAACACAUCAGAGGCCUCUAAAAAUCACCCAUUAAUUCAGGAAGGCCAAGGAGAAAGGCCUUAUAGAGACGUUGAUAUGUUGGAUGUGCCUAGGCUUUCAGAGCCACCCUUUCCACAACACCCCUCCCUGCAAAGUAUUUAUUUCACAUCUGCACUGUCUGGCACAGAUGGUAGAUAGUGCUGGUUUGUUCAUUUUAUUUUUUUACUUAAAAGGCUAUUUUGAGCCCUGUUUCUUUCACUGUCCAGUCUAGUCCUCUUUGAUUAUAUCAGUAGUUGCUGAGUAAGAAAGAAGCCAGGGUGACCAACGGGCCUUUAAAAGUGUUGUCUCCUCUACUUAUGCUGAAAGAGAAGGCAAUUAAAUAAGACUAGUACCUCCCAGGAGGAUUGGACUGGGAUAUUUUUAACCCUUUAAAAAGAAUAGCUGUUUCUAUGUUAAAAUACCAAAGAACAUGGAUAAACCCAACAUUCCAAAGUAGUGAGUCCACUAAUGAGAAAAAUAAUAGAAUGACUUUGGUCACCUCUCGGAGACUUCUGUGUCUAUAAGGAAUCCCAGGCUGGAGACAUUCCUAGCCCUCUGUAUUGAUUCAAAAAUACUUAAUAAAUUAAAGCUGUUGAGACUUAUUUUUUCUUCUGUCACUCAGUAACCAUGAUCCUUCCUCAUUUAAUAAACAUUUGGUGACUGAAUGAGUAAUUAAAUGCUGGUUACCCACUUAAUGUGCCAGGUAGUAUGAUACUUUCUGGGGACUAAGCCAUGAACAAAACAGUCUAGAUCCCUGCCCUCAGAAGGGUUACAGUUUAUGUGAUUACUAUUUUCAUGAGUAAAAGUGAAGAAAGCCAUAUGGAAAGAUUUUUAUCUUGCAAGAAAAAACAAUUAUGAAACUCUUUUAACAUAAACACACUGAAACUGUAUCAAAGCAAUUGUCCAAAUUGUAUUUAUACCCAAGAAUUUCUUUAACUAAGAGAGCAUAAGGCAUAUGUUUGGAAAACCACCCUCUUUAUCUUUGACCGACUUGCAGAUAAAUAUAUCUCUCCAUUUUAAACCAAGAAGGGCAAUCAUGUUGGUGAUCCAGAUCACUGAGAAAGCCCAGUGUAUCCCAUCUUUUAUCUUUGUUGGCAAUGGAACUUUUCUAUGGCCCACACUUUACAAUUCUUUGUCAUUCUAACCCAUCCUUCCCAUCCUUAUUUUUUUUUUUUUUGAGAAUUGCUAAAUGGAAAGCUAGCCUAGAAGCACCAAGUAAAUAUAUUCAAGGAAUAUAAGUUGUUUAAACAUUAGAAAAAUUUUUGCACUCAUUUUUUAGCUGUAUUAGGAAUGUCAAUAAUCCUGUAGCAAAUUUUCACAGAGAACUUUAAGAAAUUCUUGCAUUGGUCGAUUUCAAUUUGAAAGCUUUUUGGUUUGUUUGCUUUUUAAAUUUUCAUGUUCUAGGAAACUAUGAUUCUGGUUGUUCAGGAUUGUUAUUAUUAUAGUUGUGUAAAAUUAUUUUAUUUUGUGUGUAUUGUGCACAGCUUGGGGGGGGGGCGGGAAAUGCACUAAUUGUGCUCUUCCUUAUAAAUGGUACAUAUUACUGACACAGACAAAUAAAGUUUCUAAUUGUUUCUGAUUUAAUCACUAGUGAUACAGCAUAUUCUGUAUGAAAUGUUUUCUCCUUUCUCAUUGUCAUCUACUUCAUUUUUUGUUUUCAUGUUUUGAAGAAAUAAAAACCAAAAUGGUAUUAUUGUGCAACUGGUAUCAUCAUCCAAAGAAAAAAACAGACACCAAGUAUUCAAACUCUUGCAAACGUCAACCCUUCGGUCAUGCAAUGUUCUCUUUUUAAUGUCCCAGGAGAACACAGUGUCAGAAUAUUUGUCUGUCCUACAGUGCUGAGAUAUAUGUUGGACAUUCCUCCAUUUCACUGAUUUUUUUUACGUUGCUUAGUAUGACUCUAUCUACAUCCUUUCCUGCAUCCAGGAUCAUAAGCCCAUAAACAGUUACAUGUCAGACAACUUUUUAGCAUGCAGAGUAUUACAUCAAAUCAGUCGAUCCCAAAAAAUUCCAAUCCCAAAAUUGAUGGUAGUACAGUUUCUUCCCAAGGGGAUGUUUAAGUAAAUUUCUCUUUUAGUUUCAUAUGUUAUAUUCCUCUUGUAGAACUUCUGCCUCGCAUUAACGAUUUCUGUCUAUAUCUUAUUAACUUCAUAUAUCAUAUAGUCAAAACAGUAUAGAAGGAAGUGAUGUCAGAAAUGGAAUAAGCAUUUGUGGGGAAAAAAUGUGACCUCUAAGGUUUGUGUACUUAUUUGAAGUUGACAUAUUAGUGGACUUAGUUCUUACUAUAAUAGAAUCUGUCCACAUGUACAAGUAAAUGCUACUUUAUUGAUCCGAUCAUCUUUAAAAUUUUCUUUAGUAUUCCUCAUUAUAUUCUUUAUAUGGUCAUAUGUGGUAUACUUUCAUGUAUGAAUGAAGGAAUUAUUUAAAUAUUUUAUAGUAUCAAACUGUCAAUAUGUCUCUUGAGUACCAGCCUUUGGUUUAACACAAAAUGAGCAGCCAACCUCUAUUUCUUUAUAUAGCAAAAAGAUUAAUUCAAUGACCAGAGCUCCUUGACCGUCUAACAACCUUUCAGAAAAAUUCUGUGACCUGAUAAUUAUCAGUUUCUUACAAGCAAAUUUUAAUGGGUUCAAAUUUCCUGAUUCCAUCCUUCAACCAGUGAGUGUUUUAUAAAAUUUUGCUUUUUGUAGUUCAUAGCCUAAUAGCACUAAUUUUUUGUUGCUUUUCAAACAUAAAAUUUUUACAAAAUAUUGUUUUAGAAACCCUGCAAAAAUUCUGAUGCAUGCCUUUCCCCUGUGGCCUCACUAUUAAUGAAAGCUCACCACUCACAUUGCAUUUUCCACAGGGGUCUUGAUUCAUUGGUGAUUCCACAGCAAAAGGUCCCUGAUCCUAAACUGUCAAAAUAAAGUAGCGAGACUGAUAUACAUCUGAUAACUUUGUGGAAGCAAUUAGAAAAUUUUCUCUGGUAGAUGAUGAUGCCCUCCAUCCUCUAAUAGUGGCAGAACUUUGCCUUCUCAAGAGAAUAAAUCAGCCCCUUUAAGACUUCUUUUAAUAUUUUUGGGCUGGGGAUAUGGAGUCUCUCUGUUGAUUCUGACUUUCUGACUAUGAUUUUGGGCAGUUGCAUGCAGAGCAAGUUCUGAGUGUAGUUUCAUAAUCUCAAGAACGUUUGGCCAUUUUAUGAUUGACAGCAUGUAAUAUUGGAUCUCACCUGACCUACAACUGGCAUUCAGCUUUUAUCAUUGUAAUCACUUCACUUGGCCAAGGCAGUUGGUAAAACUGAGCAAAGUUAAAUAUAAAUUCCAAUCAUUAAAUUGGUGAGUGCAUUAUGCAGAAGAUACAGAAUCCUAUUUCAGAAAAAGAAACAUGCUAUUAUAAGUGGAUUCCUUAGAUUUUGUUCAGCUCUACCUACGGAGUUUUGCUAAUAGAAUGUAGUUCUGCUAUUCUUUUUUACCAUUAUGUACUCACCACUUCUAACCAUCUUGUUGUCUUCCCAUCACGCAGUACAUUUCAAAAUGCUGGGCGGUCCCGAUGGUAUUACACCCACAAGGACAGCAUAGGAAGGGUAAACAAUUGAAAUAGAUAUUUCAUGUUGGGAGCUUAAUUAGGCCAUGAUUAAUCGUCUCUCAAAGCAGAGACUGUCUUAUCUAUAAAAGGAGCAACCACUGAGAGGUGGAACUCCCAAAGGAAAGCACUGCAGGUUUCCAGCCCACAAGAAAUGGUACGUAUUUCACUUUCUUUGACUUUUUCCCUGCCUGUCAAGAUGUCCAAAUGUACUCAGAGGCUGUCCACAUUUUCAGUUUUGUCAAAGGUUCUCUGAUUCAAUUUUGUAAGAAACAUUUAAAUCAGUGGUUAUGUAAAUUAUUGUUUAUUUUGUUUUACUUUUAGGAAAGAGCAUUACUGUAUAACUUCAAAAAGCAAUAUGACUUAGUAGUUAAAAUUAUGACCCAUAUUUUUUCAGGAAGACUUGCUUGCCCAAAAUUGUCUUGUCUAUCUGUUAUCAAUGUAGUCAUUCAUAGCUGCCUCAGUGGUUCACAUUUUUUAGAAUUAUGCUUCCCUAGCAUUUUUUCAAAGAGUUGGAGAGUUUUCCCCAUGGGAAUAAACAGUCUUAAUAUUUCCUUUCCCUAAUUUCAGCCUUUGCAGUUCUUCGGUGACUACUCCCAUUAUAUCCAACUACCCUUAGUGAUGCUCACUAUUACCUCCCGGCAAUAGGGAAAGAGCUUAUGCUAUAAAGUGAUUGCUCAAGACAUGUUUUUCUGAAAGUGAACUUAUCAUAGGAGAAAUCAAAUAUAAUGACAUUCCACCUAGAUAAGAGUCACUAGGACAUAGUAUGGAAUCUUUGUAAAUGAGCGGGACAGAUCAUACCUACAGUUACACAUAUAAUAGUGUUGUUUAUUUUAUACCUCUUGAAUCAUAUUUAUUAUGCUUCAGUGCUGCCCAUCGACCUAGCCUUUUAUUCUAUCAAUAUGUAGGUGUGGAUUGGGAAUGAGAACCGACAUUCACAUCCCUGAUGCUCAUGAGGGUUUCUACAAAGGUGGAGUAUGUAAACAUAGAAAAACGUAACAGAUAGCUUCCAUGCCUCUAAGAAAUAUGAGUGGGUCAAAUGCUUCUCUGUGGGUACUAUUUUUCUGCUAUGCAAAUGGUAGAAAAGUUCACAUUAAUAGCCAAACAGACCAAGAGAGAAAUUAGCUAACUUCACUGUUAAUCUGUCUACUUUGACAGUUAAGAUAUAGCCCAGCCCUCCUAAUUUGUUGACUGCAAAGACAGAUACGCCUAGUUAAAUCCAAGAAUGCACUGGGGGACGGGGGGAUAAAGUUACUAGAAUAAUUAUACAACCCUCCGUACUAAGAUUGCUUAUUCGCCAAGAAGAAUCCUGCCCAGAGAUUUUCAGAGACAUUUCCUUACAUUCCCAACCUUCUUUUAAUUUACACAACUUUUUAAUUAGACCCCUUGAAGCCACAUAGUAAAACAAGAGAUGAAUUAUCUAAGGAGAACUUUUGGCCCUCCCUCUAAUGUGAAGAUCACAUACUUGACUGUAUUUCCCAUUCUUUCCAAAUGGAAAGAACAGUCCAAUUAAGUAACCAACUAUGUAACCACUUUUUGACGUAAUUCCACCUAAAAAACAAAGAGUGAACUAAAUUGUACAAACAUUAAACCUAACAGUGAUAUGACCAGAUGGCUAGUUUUGAGAAAAAUAAUAUUUUCUGUAGAUACCUUGCUCUCCCUUCCUGUACUCAUCCUAAUGCUCAAGUUUGAGAAAUACUCCAAGGAAGAAAUCUUGAAAGAUUGUACAUUCAAAUAAUGCUCAUGUAAUUGAGUAAUAUGGCAUUUGGGAUGAGAAUAAGAGCGUAUUUAAAAAUAAGAGAAUUGGCACAAAAAUGUGUUAACUAGGAUUUUAUUACAAAUUGCCCUAAGAUAUUUGCAAGUUAUUAUAUUUAAGUGAAAUAAAUCCCAGUUUCCAGAAACAACAGUACAAUUUAUAUUCGCAGGUUUUAUAUGAAAAUCAAAGUUGGGCAUACAUACUUUUUGGCUUUGGCAACCAAAGAAAAGCAUGUUUUUGGCACACGUUUCCAAAUUAUUGAGUUAUUUGUAGAAUACAUUGGACCUGUACAGGUAUCUCAUUAAAAUUACCUUCAAUAAUUUCCCUUUCUUCCUUUAAGCCAUCAAGUUUCUAAAUUUUACAACUUCACAGUUUAGCAAUUUCAUUUAUGAAAGGCUGAUUCCAUUUUGAUGUUGAUUUUUACAUUUCAGAAUUUUUCAUAUAUAAAUAUUUGAUGCAUUAGAUGGGAUACUGAGCUUGAGUCUGGCCCAAAUGAACCACAAGGCCCAGACUGAUCUAUCAGUAGUUAGAAGGCUUCUAAUACACUGGCUUUCUAAUGUACAGUAAAUACUAGCGUUGUUUUCAAUAUUCUUUCUUUUGACUAAAAGUUUCCAUUCCAACUGGUGAAAAAUUUUUAAAAAAUAUUUAUAAUGAUAGUUAGAGAACUGUUUAUAUGAGGAUCAGACAUUGUUUCAGCACUGGAUCUCCUCUGUCCCCUCUCUUGCUACAGCAUACAGCCCAGAGACACACAUGUAAAAGUAGGUGAUCUCUGUAAACUUCAGCUGCAUUUCUGUAUGUCUAGGAUUGUCCUAGUAUCAGAUAUCCUUUGAGAAAGAGUUGGAGAGGCAUGGAAGGAAGCAUAUUCCUGACCUCCCCCCUUUUUAGCUAAAGAUACAAAUUCAGAGCUGUUUGAAAAGGGCUUAGAAUAAUAUUAAUUAAACAUAUUCUAUAAUACAAAGAGAAGUACUUUUUUAAAAUACAUUUAUUUUUCUUUCUUUUUUAGCAGGCAUUUCUGACAGAAAAUCUUUAGGGCCAAUUAGAGUUUCUUUCUGACUUUUAAUUGCCCUCUGCCUUUUGGGAAAGUGUUGAAAAAAGCUCUGGAAAAAAAUAUGCUGGUCAAGGUCGAACCCUGGGGAAUUAAAAACAUGAGAUUUUUAUAUUUUCCCUCCAAACAUAGCACUGAGCAGGCAGGUUCCCAUGCCUGUUGUUAAUCGGCAUUUUCUUUUUUUUUUUUUUUUUUUUGAGACGGAGUCUCGCUCUGUCGCCCAGGCUGGAGUGCAGUGGCGGGAUCUCGGCUCACUGCAAGCUCCACCUCCCGGGUUCACGAAUCGGCAUUUUCUAAACACGUGUUUUGGUGUGCUGGGAGCAGAGGAGUAGGAGGCCCACCCAGUCCCACCACACAUACCGGGACAUCUUUGACCACAUGGGUCCUCUGCCGUUCGUAUUUUAGCUUAGAUGUUCUUAACUGAACUAACUUCCAAUUUUCAUAUACACUGAUCAUCUUGUCCCUAGCAUUUUCCCUCCAAGAUCCUGCUAACAGGCAAACUAGCCCUUUCAAACAGUUGGUACCUGAGAUUUCUCAGAGCUCUCUUAUCAAGAGUAAGGAGUGAGAUUGCAGAAGGGGCAGUAAUGUCAAUACCAAGUUAUUGGAAACUACUUAACCAGCCACUGCAUUACAUACUGGAGCCCGUCUAGGACACUUGCCCUUGGAAAUGGUGGAAAGACUUUGUUUUAUUUCUAUUUCAUCAACAGAACUUUUGUAGCAUUGAAUCUAAGCAAAGGAUAACAUCAUAUUAUAAUGGAAAGUUAUUUUUAACUACAACUGUUAUUGUUAAAUUUAGAAGAAAAUAUUGUCUUUGAAGUUUCAGUCCAAAACUCUAAGGAGAACAAGGUUUUUACUGCCAUCGGUAAUCCUGUGAGAAAUUUGACACUCCAGAUCUUAUUUGAGACAGAUAAGUCUAUGAUAAAUAUAUGUAUGAGACUUAAAAUAUUCUUGAUAUUCUCAGGUUGUUCUCACAAAUUCUGCAUAGAUUUAGUUGUUUUUUUUUUUAUGAGAACCUUUCUUAUCAAAAAGGAUUGAAAAUUUUUCCAACAACUGGUUGUUAAAUGAGUCUAGCACCCAAAGAAGCUGUGAGCAGUUGGUUCUACCAGUGACUCUUCUAGGAGCUCUUUCCAGGUUGGUCUCGAACUCCUGACCUCAGGUGAUCCGCCUGCCCUGGCUUCCCAAAGUGCUGGUAUUACAGGCAUGAGCCACUUUGCCCAGCCUGAUAGUUCUGACUCAAUCCCUAGACACAUUCUUCAGAAACAACUGUACAUGGUGAGAGAAAAGUGAAAAGGAAAAAAGUUUUCCUUCCUUCAAAAUACACUAAAUUUGCUUAUCACCUUUAAAAUUUGGACUGAAUGUUUAAACUUUAAACACAAAGCAAAGGGAGAUGCUCUUAAAUGUGAAAUCUGAAGCAAAGAUUGCAUUUUUGCAAAGCUAUCCAGAAGAUGUGUUAAUUAUUGAGACAUGGGAUUCAUUAACACAUCAGCGCCCAACCACUGCCUCUCCUGCCCCCAUUCACACAUUAUCCACAAUCAAAUAAGCAGCUAAGCAGGGGAAACCUAUCACUGUUAAUGUCAUAAUCACAUCACCACUGAAUUACCAGAUGUGGUCAGGAACUAGGCAAAGUAGGUGGGACCAAUCCUAGGACUGGGGCCAUACCACAACCUCAGCUCAGCCCCUUGUCGGAUACGGUUUCUGAAUUUAGUACAAUGCCAGAAGUAUUUUUUUUCUUUCAGCUGUGAACCAGCCUGUUUUGUUUGACAAGCCUUUCCAGAUUCAUGCAGCUCAAUCACGUGCUUGUUGCCAGUUUGAGAGUGAACCUAUUAUUUCAAACUUGUUGCCGUGACCAAUUUUUACAAAACUGAAAGUAGCACUGUGAGGUGGAUUGGACCUAGUGAUGAGGUGUCUACACUUGCAUCCUUUUCUUCCAAGAGAAUAUUCUGACACUCCAACUCUAGAAGUCAUGUCAUUAGUAAAAUGAAAAUAAUAAUUGCUUAAUCACUGUUUAGAAUUAGUUCAUACUUCUUCAGAGCUUGAAGCCUCCACGACUCAACAUCAGAUCCAUGGAUAGUAUUACUAUACCUUUACCCAAAGACUGGAUUUAUUUUGUAAAAAUAUCAGAAUGGGUCUGGGUCCCUUUAAAGCAACUGACAAGGUAUUUAACAACAUUUUAAAACAAUGAAGAAAGGAUGAUUCUGCAGAGGCUGCUGGGUUACAGAGGAGGGCAGAGCUUUUGUCAGACUCUCUUGAUGUUUUGCUCUUCCUGGUAAGUUUUUAUCUAUCAUGGUUCCCAGUGGAAUAUUCUCCAUACACAUUCUGUGGGAGGAUAUUGACAUGGCUCUAGACUCUGCCUUUUAUUUUCUAAUUCUCCUUGGAGAAUUAGAACAGGCAUUCCAGAACUUGUAAUAUAGAGGGGAAGAAAGAAAAAAUGGCAGAUGCCUCAUUGAUGGAUCCACAAGUUUUGUACAAAAGCACACACCAUUCUGAUUGUCUCUAUAUUAACAUUGUACUCACCAAACAGCUUUCUAAAGGUGACUGGAACAAGAUAAAUAUCAACUGGAUAAUUACCUAAGGAAAAAGAAUAAAAAAGAAAUCAAACCAAAAAAAAAGCAAAAAAUUGGUCAGUUUAGCAAGCGUGUUUUCCAGGAUCAUAGGCUCAUAAACUAUACAGUCAAGAGAGUGAAACAAUUUUAAAAUCAAAAGUUAGAGCCUUUUAUAUUUCUUCAGAUGUACAAUUUCAUAAAUCAAGCAUUUAUUUUGUGCAAAGUAUUAUAUUAGGUACCCUAAAUGGUAUAUAAAGAAUUCAAAACAGAGUAAUUUAAGAAAAUUAACACUAGUCUUUGAUUUAGUCAGGAAGAGUCCACUUAUGGCAUUCUAAUUAAAUUAACCUUCCAUUUUGGUCUACAUUUUAUCAAUUUGAGAUUGCUUAAUGGGGCCAUUUUGAAACCUAUCAAGAAACUUUCCUCUAACAGAAAUAGAAAUAUUAAUUUUCUUAAUUUCACAUUCUGUCUUCCACUAAUAAGAUAAAUGGAUUCAGACCCAACACACACAUCCAGAGAUUACCAUGAGCCAAGACCUGUGUAAGUUUGAUAUAGGGUCUUUUAUUCAACAUUUCAAGUUGGGAAAAUCUUAUUACAAAGAUCAUUUGCCUCACCAUUGCUGAAUUCUUUUACUAGGUGUUGAUGCUAAUUCAUCACUGGAUUUUCUUAACUCUGCCUGUUGCUCUUUUGGACUUUGAGGCAUGUGGUUCUAUUUCAGUGAGUUACAACUCCAGCUCUCAUCUUUUAACAGCAAACUAGAGAACAUCUCACUCUUCAUCUCUGAGGACACAGUGUUCUCUUCAUUUUAACAUCAAAAAGUCACCAGAGAGAAGACCCAAAGGCUUUUCUCUUUGGAAAAGGAAUCUUUAAUUGUUUCAGAGGGUGAGGAAUCUUCAGCUCUCUCUGGACUUGAUUGUCCUCAUCAUUAAAUGGGAAGACUUUACCUUUAGCUUGAUUUUCCAGAACACAUCAAGCCCCGUAUGGUCAGUGUUUCCCUGUUAUCAUCCACUUAUGUGUAUGGGUUGAAGGUACUUUAAGUUGUGAGCCAGCUGCUGCCCAUAUUGGGUCACCAAUGCACUUGUCAAGCCCAUGUAACCACAUGAAGUUUGAUAGAAAUAUAAACAUUUAUUUUGAAAUAAUUCCAUGUGCACGGUUGGAAAAACAGUCUCCCUUCCCUGAGAGGAAUGAGUAAUUUCUCCCUUUUCAAGAAGUGUACAGUAGAAAAUGUAAUGAGAUUGGAAUGGAUUCCAAAUCAGUGACCUUUUUAAGGCUGAAACCACUAUUUUAAAUGAAAACUUUAAGUUCAUACAGUUUCUUAUAGUAAUUCUACUUUUAUUUUUUAGUCAGUGUGCUUAAUCUUUUAGGAAAAAAAACUAACCAGUUAUUUUUUACUAAAGUAUGUGAAUUACAAACAGGAUGUGCAAUGACCAGGCAGAAAGAUAUUUAAAGGUGUAAUUAUUCUAAAGGAAGAUGAGAAAAAAUUCAUCUGCUACAGAUUCAACUGUCUUUUAAAUGCCUCCCUUGUCAUGGAGUAAAUGACUACUCAAAAGGAUUUCACAAAAGACUUAAAUCUCACCCUUAGCAAUCAACCGGUCGGCCACAGCUCAGAUGCCUCAUUAGCAAAAUGAAAUUGCACAACAGACGAAACAUAGCAAAAGAAUGUAGACAUUUCCAUGGGGUGGAAGAAAAGAAGAAAGAAAAAGCAACCAUAGUGAACUCUGCUUGCAUAAACAAAGAAUGUUUUAGUGGAAUAAAUGUAAGCUUUCUCUUGAAGGAAUCCCAGUUAGAAUGUCAUUGGAAACGGCAAAACUAUUUCAGCUUCAUAGCAGUAAUAUAUUCCAACUUUAUUACCACUGAGGCACAAAGCUAAAUUUGUCAGGGGGAAAGGUAAGCAAAAAUUACUGACAUUGCAACCGAUAAAAUGAUCUUGUGAGACUCAAUAUUGAGAAAGAAAAUUAAAAUAGCUAAUAUUUCUGUUAUAAUUCCAGUGAUUACUAAGACUUCUGCCAAGGGAUAAAAUUACUUUUCCUUCUCUCAUUAUAAAUUUCUAUAUAGAGCUAUUUUAAUGCAGUAAGGACUGUAUUUUCAUAUUUUAAUAAAUCCCUCACGUUGAAUUUGCCCCCCAUUUCAGAUUUGAUUAGGAAAUACUAAAUUGAGAAGGCAGGUUUUUCCAUCUUUUUAAAAACAAGUAUGCACCAUAAGCAUUUUCAGCGGAUGUCUGCCUUAAGCAAUCUUGGUAGAGCUGUCAAUCAGUGGCAGGUGCUUGUUUAAGGAAGAGAACCUGUGAAUAGAUUUAGCCUUUCUUCCUCACAGACAGCUGCUCAUUCACACACGCUCAUCUCGUCUUCCUCAACUUCUUGCACCAAUCCCGCCUCUUGGAUUGACCCACAUCCACCUAGCAGUUGAACAAACUGCAGAUUCUAAUUACAUGUCCCGACAGUUGCUCAACUUAAUUUUUCACCAACUGAAUUUCAUGCAUUGCCCCUUGAUGUUCCUUCCCUCUGUUCACUCUUUUCUAUAAGUCCUUGCAUUUGAUAUACUUUAAAAUGGAUUUGACUAGGAAAAAAAAAAAAACCAAGUCAGCAAACCCUUGUGUUCAUUCAAGAAAUUGUGAACAAAUUUAGCUGUUAUGGUAAUAAUCCUGAGGUGAGAGAGAAAAUAUCACCUAGGUGACAAGAGAUCAUUUUAACGCUAUUACUAAAAUAGUAUUCUAUGAAUAGAGGCCAUAGAAUUUUCUACAAAUAGACUUGUAGGGACUCACAUUUUGAAUCAUAUUUUACUUAUAGGUUUGCUGUAUAUACUGAUUAAACUUCUGAACCUAAAGAUUCUCUAUAAUUAAACUAGCACAAAUAUAAUCUGUCCCUUACCCACAUUGUAAGAAUGUCUGGUGGGGGAAAUCCAAUAUUGACCUUCACAUUCCACAUGGAAAAUCUUUGUCCCCAGAGUGCAAUUAGGGUGAUUAAAAAUAAGCCGCUUUUGUGAGUCUCAAGUUUGUUCCCCAAACAAGCAGCAUCAGCAACUGGAAAUUUGUUAGACAUGCAAAUUAUCCAGUCCCACCUGAGACUUCAGCCCAGAUCUAUGAAUCAAAAAUUUUGGAGUGACCCUGGCAAUAUGGACUUUAAUAAGCCCCUAGGAUGGUUCUGAUGCAUGCUCAAAUUUGAGAAUCAUUGAUCUAUGACACAGCAUUCUGAGUGGCCAAGAAUGAACAAUGUCACCCACUGCUUAAUUAUGCUUUCCCUUAAGAAAAGGUUUAAAUGCUUAAAAGGUAGGUUCUUUAUAAAGAUAAUGCAUUCAGAUAUAUGGGAGAUAUGUCCACCAUUCAGACUUAAAAUAUAAUUUUAAGGGACAUUAAUCCUUAUGUCUUUUUCUGGCAUAACUGAGUCUGAGGCAGCCUCUCCAGUCAGAGAUUUCUAAUCAGCUUAUCUAGUUCUUUUAAAACCCCACAGCUGAUCUACUUUGCCUGACUUCCCCGGGGCCUAGAAAAUGACCCUGGACACCUUUCUCUAACUGAUUAGCUCUGGCUGAUUUGUCUUAAUGCUAAACCACUGUGUAACAGUACUAAAUUAUACUUAAUGACACAGUCUACUGUUUUGAAGAGUGCUGUGUAUGACUGACUGAGCUAAAAGGAUUGCUGGCUAUGAGUGAGUUUUAGUUUUAGAAUUCAUUUUCAAAGACUCACAAGGCUCAAGAAGCUUGAAAACCACAGAUGAUGUAUACAGUAGCUGGAGUUCCCUGGAGGCUCCUUUCUAGGGUCUCUCAUUUGAAUUGGUGCAGAACUGAAAGCAGAGAGUCAGAAAGUAACUCUGCUUGUAAAAAUGGCUUAGGAAAAGGAACUUAAGAUUGUGGGUUAUAUGUGUGUAUGUGUGCACACACAUGUAUGUUUCCUGAAUUCUAACCUGAAAAUAUCACAUUUGUGGAUACUUAAAAUACUCAUAUGCAUUUUGAUACACAAAAGCAAUUCAAAGUAUGUAAAAGGAGGCUGGAAAUGUAAGCUUAACAGUGAUAUUCUGGAGAAAAAUGUUGUAACUGUCACUCCAGGCCUCCCUUAGGAGAAACCAAACUUGUCAGAUAUUUUGGAAUGGUAGCUCUUUUUCAGGAAUUAGAAUAACUGAAGUAUGAUACUGUGUUCCGUGUGCUUUAAAAUCUGUGACCCUCCCCUGUUGCUGGUCAUAGCUUCAGCAUUUGAGUGUCCAUUGUCUGUCGCUGAGGACAUUUUCUCAUCGGCUCUUUUCCCCAUUGUCCCAUUCCUCUCACUCACACCUGAUUACCAAAUAGCUCUAACGAAAUCACAGUCACUCCUUCCUGUGUUUCCACCAUUGUGUACAUCUUCAUUUGCACACCCUAUUUUUUAAUCAAAGUUAAAGCCUCACCAACAAGGUACUUAGAACAAUCACCCACUUCUGGCCACUUCGUGACGGGAAAUACAUCUUUGCAGGGGAAGGAGCUGGAUCAGACUGACAGGGUUUCACUCAGACUAUUUCAAACAAUGAGGAGCCUUGACCUCAUUCCCAACUUUUGCCGUCCAUAGUGGUUGAUUUCUUGUUUUCUCUUUCUCUCUUUUUUUAACAGAAACUCUUAAGCUCAAGGCUAAAUUACAGUGGGGACUUGCCUUUGUCUACAGUCCAUGGUUUCUGUAUUGGCUCAAGCCUUGAAAUCUUGAAACAAGCCUAAAUUAAAAUUUUCUCUUAGCUUAAGAAAAAAAGUUACAUAUUGUCAAGACCCUUAUGUGUGUGGUCCAUUAAAAAGGUCUUGAUAUUAGAAGAUAACAGCAAAUUGUUUCUUAUCCCACAACAGCUUUGCCUUUCAGUGUCCUUUGUGGUGGUUUUCGUAGGUCAGUGGUACAAUUCAACACUCUUCCAAUAAGCCAUAAUAAUAAUUGUUGGCACAACUGUUAUUACAACAGGACUUGCCUGGGUUCCAUCUAUUAAUUUUUACAGACAGUAGGAAGCUCACACCGAGGAGACAUUGGUAACUUCCUGGACAAGGGCAAAGAAAGGAACUAGCAUAUUGUACAUACUGUGUACGUGCACAGAACACUGGUCUGUGCCUUUGGAGUGUUCUCAGAGGGGCAGGCCAGAAGGGAGGAUUCAGGUAGGAAAUGAAUCUAGGACUUCUCUUGCCUUUGAUGGUUACUGAUGGCAAUUGUGUUUCCCACUGAAUAACUUGGUGGACAAUUUUGAUAGUAAACUGAACUCAUACCGAGCAAGCACAAUAGUCAAUCCAUAAAGAAAAGGGUGGCAUAUCAUAAUGCCAGAAACCUUGUCUCCCUAAGAGGUGAUCAUGAAUUUCCUAUACAGGGCAAAAAAGGGAAGAAUAGCCUAUUCAUAUUCUGUAUUCACAGUUUGAAGGACCCAUCACAAAUGACCUUCAAAGACUGACAGGGGGCAGGUAGAAGGGAGGCAAAAAUGCAGAGAAAAAGAUGUUACCUUGAAAAAUGAAGUAAGAAAUCCUAAUAUUCCCGUAGUUGAUCCUAAAGUUUGUUCCCAUGUCUACGGUUAUUUCUAAAUAACUUCACUACACUUUGAAAUUCCUUAGUGGUGGUUUAUCAGUAAUACUUAACUGAAUUUUUCCGUUUCUAUUCUUUGCUGCCAAUGAAUGUAAUCUCCACGACUUGCCGUUCGAGUGCACGCACAGACACACACACAUAAUGGUAUAUGCAUCAUAUAUUACUCAUUUUGUGGGAAACACAAUGUAUUAUAAUGAAAAAGAUUCCAGCACAUUCUUUCAGUGUGUUUCAGUGAUAAAAUUUUGUGGGGGAAUAGAGGUAUACAUACUCUCUUUGCUGACCAUAUUGUUGAAAUUAUGAUCUUAAGCAACACUGUUAGAAAUGCUUGCAUAAAGUAUCUUCUCUAGUAUUAAUGAGUUGAUUCACUCUGAAUUGAAGGUUCAAAAAAAUGCACUAAACAAAUAUUUUUAUAUCUGUGGUAUUUUCCUAUUAACUACUCUUAGUGAACACGUGACCAUAUACCUGAUAUCAUUAAAAAGGAAAAUGGCCUAAACGAAACGUUAAAAGUGGAGGUAUUUAUAAAGUCUUCUGCCAAAGACCAUUGUUUAAUGAUCUGUAAAAUGUAGAUUAUCUUCUUUUAUUAUGAAUGUGAUUGUAAGAAACACCCUAACAUUCUCUAACUUUUGAAAAUGAAUAUUUUGUAUUUCUAAGGACCAAGGAAAAUAUUUUUUAAGCCAAUGUAGUACACAGAAGCCUUGUAAAUGAGAGGUACAAUGACUUGGAUCAACUGCAUAAUGCUAGAUUAGAAUUCCAGCAUUUGAUGAUAAAUUUAUCAAUCUUUCCUAUAAUUCUUAUACUGCACUAAAUUACAUUUUGGAAAUUUUAGCUAAUCUUUUCAAAUUAAAGGCACCAACAUUAAUGACAGAUCUUCUCUAAUAUGAAAAGCAUCAAAACAUUCCCUUUCAAGCACUUUGAAUGGAUGAAAAUUGCCAUAUAAUUUUCCCACCUACCUAACCAUUCCAUGUAAGUUAACUGAGCAGUCUAACAAUGUUGUACAGAAGGUUGACAGACUAUGUGCACCAAGAAUAUUUAAGUUGUGCAGUUAGCAAGAACUAGCCAUUUCAAAUAUACUCAAAUGUUUUGUAAAUAAAAAUUUUGACUCCUAUAAUUUUGUUCAAACUGAUGUCUUUUAAAAUAAUUAGAUUUUAUUUGAAUUUUAAAAGUAAUCUGUUGUAAAUUAGAUGUUACUUUGUUGACUCUGUGAUUCAAUGUACACUCAGCCAUAUUCCUGUGGGGAAAUAUCAAUCUUACUGACUUUCAUGGCAUGAGCCAGAGAUUCAUAGUUUCCUUUAGGACUAUAAGUAUGAAGACAAAACACACCAAAAUAAAAUGCUAGUGAAGAAAUUAGAAACCUAUUGUAUAAAAUGUAUUUUUAAAAUCUUAAGAUAUAUGUGAUUUACACUGCCUGUUAAUCUAGUCUCUUUGUGAUUAAAAAAAAACAUAAUAUUUGUUAAGACUCAGACACCAAAUAUUUGUGAUGUUUGUAUAGCACCAUCGUUAUAUGUGAUUUCAAAGGGUAAGCAUCUCUGUCGUAAUCAUGUAAGCCCACAGAAGAAUAAAUUCCUGAGGUUAUGUACAACCAACUCUCAGAAUUCAGACUUCCUGCAGCUGCCAUAUCACCAAUAAAUGAGAAUUGUGAAAAACAAUUUUUAAAGAAUUGAGUUUAUGAUCACUGUGCAUUUUGUUAAUGAAUGAUUUCAGAGUUUUAUUUUUACCAGAAAUGCUCUCAGCCAGUAAACACAACUGCUGAUUUCAACCAUACUAUCAUUUCAAUGGUUUCUAUAUUCUUGAUCUAACUACCAAAAACUGGAAGCUUGUUGCAAGGUGUGUCCUAACAAACAUACAAUAAAUGACUCUUCCUGCAUGCUGCCUGAGAUAUGUUGUAAUUUGAAAUGUCUUAUCAAAAAAUUAUACAUGUUAUAACCCAAAGUUGAACUGGCAAUAUUUUUCAUGUGUAAAAUUGAUGGUAUGUUAAUAUCAAAAGCAGAAGCAUUGUUUGUCAUACAUGUAUGUUAUAUGUGAUGUUUAAUCGUGUUAAACUGUAAUCUGUGAAGUUUUCAUUGCCUGAACUAGUCAAUUCUGUAUAAAUCAUUGUCUUAAUUGUUUUCCUAAUCUUACCAUAUUUCCUAACACUGAAAUAUAAAUGUUUGUCAAUUAGCCA